GCUCCAGCCCCACAGUCCUCUUUCUGCUUCUUUCCCAGCCUCUGGGCUUUUGCACACGCUGUUCCUUCUGCCUGAACACCCUCCACUGGGCUGAGAACAACUCUCUGAGACCUCUCUCAGCUGUUGCUUCCUUUGGAAAAGCCGCUGCUGCUGUCCCUCUCCCAGCUCAAAGACCUGCUGAGCCUCCUGUCUUUUUCAGUUCCCAUGCCCCCAGCACUUCUCCUUGGCCUCCUUUGGCCCAAUUGACAAUGUCCAUUCUCAAUGCCUUCCCACCCAGCGCUGAGCCCCACUGGGUGAAGGCAAUGCCUGUCAUGUUCACCACAAUAUCCCCUCCCCCAUCACCACGACUGGUCCACAGUGAUGCUCAAAAAAGAUCUGUUGGUAGGCAAUGCGAAGGUGCAUUCAUGUCAUCCUGCAGGCGGAAUUCUCCACGAGUUUUGAGCAGCCUCGGGUUUCCCACCACCUCCAAAUCAUGGAAGACACAGGUUCAGGCAGAGCCCGCGGAGCCAUGGCCAGCCCUUCCAGCAGCUCCGAAGCCACUGGCAAGCCCCGAGGCAGGGAUGGCAGUCCCAGGAUGGGGGAGGAGGAAGUCCCUCCCGAAGAGAAGAGGCUGGGGCUGUAGCUGGAGGGGGGAAGCGCACAGCCCGAGGACUGCGAGGACGGGGAGGACCCGCCGCUGCCGGGCAGGAAGGAGACCGGCACCCAGACAGGUGGCGACGGCAAAGGAGCGGAAUUCUCCACGAGUUUUGAGCAGCCUCGGGUUUCCCACCACCUCCAAAUCAUGGAAGACACACGGUGCAGGCAGAGCCCCCCAGCCGUGGCCAGCCCUUCCGGCAGCUCGGAAGCCACUGGCAAGCCCCGAGGCAGGGAUGGCCGGCCCAGGAGGGAGGAGGACGACGUCCCUCCCGAAGAGAAGAGGCUGCGGCUGUAGCUGGAGGGGGGAAGCGCAGAACCCGAGGACUGCGAGGACGGGGAGGACGCGCCGCGGCCAGGCAGGGAGGAGACCGGCACCCAGACAGGUGGCGAAGGCAGAGGAGAAGGAAAAUACAUGUACAGCCAACUUCCUUGAGGGUUCGUUCUUUUGCAUCAGGGUGUCUCAAACUGAUGCCCUUAAAACACCUGUAAGAGAAUCAUCCAGGCGGCUUGCUUGCUCUGCAUGCAGGCCCUUUAGAAUCAGACUCAGAAUCCCUGGGGCUGGAGCCACAAAAUGAAAUGACAUUUCAACGAGUUUGUCAUCAUGUGAGAGAGAAUAGGCACAGAGAAGUUGCCCAUGACUCUGUGAUCCGUUUUGUCCAAUGAACCAUGAGCAGCAGCAACUUGAGUCACCUCCAGGUGGAAGUGUUAAGAGGCUGCUCUAUGAUCCACCACAUUCCCUUUGCCCUGAAGUGGUGAUCAAGGACACAUGCAGAGAUGGGGCUUUUGUCAGCCUGGAUCCCUGAGUGAACACAAUGAACAGACCACCCCAGAAUGCCCUAACACAGCCCAGACAUGCAACGUGACCAAGAAUAAGCCUCACUGUGGCCAGGCAUGGUGGCUCAUGCCUGUCAUCCCAGCACUUUGGGAGGCCAAGGUGGGUGGAUCAUUUGAGGUCAGGAGUUCAAGACCAACCUGGCUAACAGGGUGAAAUCCUGUCUCUACUAAGUACAAAAAUUAGCCAGACAGUGGUGGCAUGGGCCUGUAAUCCCAGCUACUCAGGAGGCAGGAGAAUCACUUGAGUCUGGGAGGCAGAGGUUGCAGUGAGCUGAGAUUGCACCACUGCACUCUAGUCUGGGUGACAGAGUGAGACCCUGUCUCAAAAACAAACAAACAAAUACCUCACUGCAUGAGGCCACUGAGAUUUGGGGUUUGUUGUUACUGCACCAGAACCCAAAUCAUCCUGACCGCUAGGGUGACCUAACUAGGGUUUCUUACCAAAAGCAAAGGCAUUUUUAAAGUUCGUGACAUUUAAACAAAAGAGCAAAUACCAAUAUCUACCACUUUGUCAGGCUAAAAAACCCAAAGAAAGCCAACAGCCAGAAGUUAAAAUAAACAGAUCAUUAGGUUGAAAAUAGAACUGUCAAAACAGGCACAAUUGACUUCAUUUAGUGAUUGCAAAGAACAUCAGGCAAGACACAGGUGUGGUCAUCAUAACAUUUAUCACAUGCUUCAUUGCACAUGUUUGACUAAGAAAAACACAAAGUAUUUAAGCUCAUCUGUAGUUCAAAGUGCCUAUCCGUGUAUUUAUCUAUUCAUCCUGAUUUAUUUAUUGAGCAACUCUUUUGUGCCAGGCACUGUGCUGUGUUGCGGGAAGUCAGGGACCCCAAAUGGAGGGACCAGCUGAAGCCAUGACAGAAGAACGUGGAUUAUGAAGAUUUUAUGGACAUUUAUUAGUUCCCCAAAUUAAUACUUUUGUAAUUUCUUAUGCCUGUCUUUACUGCAAUCUCUAAACAUAAAUUGUGAAGAUUUCAUGGACACUUAUCACUUCCCCAAUCAAUACCCUUGUGAUUUCCUAUGCCUGUCAUUACUUUAAUCUCUUAAUCCUGUCAGUCGAGAAGGAUGUAUAUCGUCUCAGGACCUGUAAUAAUUGCGUUAAGUACAUAAAUUGUACAUCAUGUGUGUUUGAGCAAUAUGAAAUGUGGGCACCCUGAAAAAAGAACAGGAUAACAGCAAUUGUUCAGGGAAUUAGAGAGAUAACCUUAAACUCUGACCGCUGGUGAGCCAGGCAGAACAGAACCAUAUUUCUCUUCUUUCAAAAGCAAAUGGGAGAAAUAUCGCUGAAUUCCUUUUCUCAGCAUGGAACGUCCCUGAGAAAGAGAAUGCGCACCUAGGGGUAGGUCUCUGAACUGGCCCCCCGGGGCGUACCUGUCUCUUAUGGUCGAGAUUGCAGAGGUGAAAUAAACUCCAGUCUCCCAUAGCACUCCCAGGCUUAUUAGGAAGAGAAAAUUCCCGCCUAAUAAACUUUGGUCAGACGGGUUGAUCUCAAAACCCUGUCUCCUCAUAAGAUGUUAUCAAUGACAAUGGUGCCAAAACUUCAUUAGCAAUUUUAAUUUCACUUCCGUCCUGUGAUCUGGCCCUGUCUCCACUUGCCUUGUGAUAUUCUAUUACCCUGUGAAGUACUUGAUGUCUGUCACCCACACCUAUUCAUAUACU